ACUGUGUGCCGCGUGCGCUGCCUGGAGCGGAGCUAUGAGCUGGACCUGUCCGCGUUGCCAGCAACCUGUUUUCUUCGCUGAGAAGGUGAGCUCCCUGGGCAAGAACUGGCACCGCUUCUGCCUGAAAUGUGAGCGCUGCCACAGCAUCCUGUCCCCUGGCGGGCAUGCAGAGCACAAUGGGAGGCCAUACUGCCACAAGCCAUGCUAUGGGGCUCUCUUUGGACCCAGGGGGGUGAACAUUGGUGGUGUAGGCUCCUACUUGUACAAUCCCCCCACUCCCAGCCCUGGCUGCACCACUCCUCUCAGCCCCAGCAGCUUCAGCCCUCCCAGGCCAAGGACUGGCCUCCCCCAAGGCAAGAAAAGCCCUCCCCAUAUGAAGACAUUCACUGGGGAGACCUCGCUGUGCCCUGGCUGUGGGGAGCCCGUCUAUUUUGCUGAGAAGGUGAUGUCAUUAGGCAGAAAUUGGCACCGACCGUGUCUGAGGUGCCAGCGUUGCCACAAGACCCUGACUGCUGGGAGUCAUGCUGAGCAUGAUGGAGUCCCCUACUGCCACGUCCCCUGCUACGGCUACCUGUUUGGCCCCAAAGGUGUGAACAUUGGCGAUGUGGGCUGCUACAUCUAUGACCCAGUGAAGAUAAAAUUCAAAUGAGACGCUCACAAAAAAGGUCACCCUAACUCAGGCCUCCCAUCAUGCCCCUCAUGGUCCAAUGGAAGCUACAAAAAUCUCCAGUCCCAUGGGGGUUGGGGAAGGUGGGAUCUUGGGGGCCUGGGCCUAGGCUCCAUGGUAGGCCAGAGAGUCUAGACUUUCUCUGCCAAUUUUUUCCCUUUCCCAUUUCUAUCUGGUUAGGGAACAGCCCGUUUUGAAGGGUAUCCUCCUCCUGGCCAUCACAACCCCUUUCCCCAGCACAUUCUGGAGCUUCAAGGUACUCAUAAAACUUGUGUUUAUUGAAUUUCAGCCUCUGUGGCUUCUUCAAUAAAAUGUUGGCUCCCA